GCACACCGCCUCCGCGGCAGCAUGGCGGACGCAGCUCCUCAACUAGGCAAGAGGAAGCGCGAAUUGGACGUGGAGGAGGCCCACGCCGCCAGCACAGAGGAAAAGGAGGCAGGAGUUGGAAAUGGUACCUGUGCUCCUGUCCGCUUACCGUUCUCCGGCUUCAGACUGCAGAAGGUGCUGAGGGAGUCUGCGCGGGACAAAAUCAUUUUCCUACACGGGAAGGUACCAGGAGGCAACCCUGAGGUGAAUGAGGCCUCUGGGGAUGGGGAUGGAGAGGAUGCCGUUGUGAUCCUGGAGAAGACGCCAUUUCAGGUGGAACAGGUGGCUCAGCUCCUGACGGGCAGCCCUGAGCUCCAGUUGCAGUUCUCCAAUGAUAUCUACAGCACCUAUCACUUGUUCCCUCCAAGACAACUGAAUGAUGUAAAGACGACCGUGGUUUACCCUGCCACAGAGAAACACCUGCAGAAGUACCUGCGCCAGGACCUCCGCCUGAUCCGAGAGACGGGAGAUGACUACAGGAAUAUUACUUUACCCCACCUGGAGUCCCAGAGCCUCAGCAUCCAGUGGGUGUAUAACAUUCUCGACAAGAAGGCUGAAGCGGACCGGAUUGUUUUCGAGAACCCAGAUCCCUCUGAUGGUUUUGUCCUCAUCCCUGACCUCAAGUGGAACCAACAGCAGCUCGAUGACUUGUACUUGAUCGCCAUCUGCCAUCGCCGGGGCAUCAGAUCCCUACGCGACCUUACUCCGGAGCACUUGCCGCUGCUCAGGAACAUCCUCCACCAGGGGCAGGAGGCCAUCCUGCAGCGCUACCGGAUGAAGGGAGACCAUCUGCGAGUAUACCUGCACUACCUGCCCUCCUACUACCACCUGCAUGUGCACUUCACCGCCCUGGGCUUCGAGGCCCCCGGCUCAGGCGUGGAGCGGGCCCACCUGCUGGCUGAGGUGAUCGAGAACUUGGAGUGUGACCCUAGGCACUACCAGCAGCGCACGCUCACCUUCGCCCUCAGGGCUGACGACCCCCUGCUCAAGCUCUUGCAGGAGGCUCAGCAAAGCUGAAUUAACUCAGGCAGAAGAGCACAGAUGUGUGGGAUUGGGGGAGGAGUGGGGACAAGAUUUUUUAUCUCCAAGUGAAUUUUCUAAAAAUGUAUUUUAUACCGGCUUAUUCCUAGUAUUGAAUAAACUAGCGGGCUCACUCAGUGUGGACAGCGUGGCCUGGGAGGCAGACAGAUGGUGGGGGACAGUGGGUGGGUAGAACCUGUGGGAAGGCCUUGAGAAUGGUGGAAAGUCUCCAGGUGGUGGUUUCAACUGACAGGUGGGAGCUGCCCUGGAAGGGUGCCGAGGGCCUUCUCCAAGCCCCAGGGCUCACCGUCCGUGGUGGCUUCCUUCUCCCCACUCUGUGCCUCUCCUGUUUGUACAACUUCUUAUUCUGCUCCUCCCCAUCACCCCUCCUCCUUCCCCUGCCAUCCACCUCUCCUUUGAGGAGUUCCCCAAAAAACCAAACUUGGAAGCUUUCAGGAAAUUAUCUAUACAGGUUUCUGAUGGCACUUCCUCCUUCCAGCAGUGAGGUCACACCUCCCUGUGAGUCAGUCAACCCUGCUGAUAAACUUCUUGUUGACGAGGAUAGGGGCUUGGUGCCUGGAAAUCGGCGGGUUUUAAUAAGAAUCAGAUUAUGCAAGGCCGAAAAGCCUGCCUUGCUCUGUUAUUUGGUCAGCGAGUCCCCAGCCUUGAGUUUUUAUCUCGGCAGGAAGACAAAACAGACUCACAUGAAGCAGCCAGAAGAUCAAGUGCAAAACAGUGAAUCAGCAAGGGCAAAUGAUAUGGUUGCAGUUGAAUACAAAAGCCCGGAGGCGGCUCGGGUUCAAGGCCUAUCAGAGGCAGAUGUUCAGAGGAUCUUGAGACCAGGAAGGGACCUCAAAGCGUCAGAGGCUGAUGAGCAGUUAGGCAGCCAACAGGGCUCAAGCGGCGCAGGGACAUGGCUUGUAUGGGCGGGCACACAAGUAAACACACAGGCUCUCUCCAGCACACAGGACCAAGGCAUCAUGCUGCCAGAGGGGCUGGUGUUUGCCACUUUGUCAGAGUAGGGCUGUGGAUUUUGUGCCUUGCUUGGGAAGCUCUCAGGGAUGGCAGGAUGGCAGGCUCCUAAGUGACAGCAGGGGGGAAGCUUGAGGCACAGUGGGUGGUCCUUACUCUCCAUCCCCUGCCUGAGAACCAGGAAGCCUCAUUCAGAGAUUAGCCCCUUUACUGCAGGUGGUAGCCCAGGUGCAGCCAACCUGCUUCAGGGUCUCAGGGCCUGCUGUGGACCCCCAUGGUCCUGGGAGAGACUCCUUAGAAACAGCAGAAUCACGAACAUGGUGAAACCCAUCUCUACUAAAAAACAGAAAAAUUAGCCAGGUGUGGUGGUGGGCUCCUAUAAUCCCACCUACUUGGGAGGCUGAAGCAGGAGAAUCCCUUGAACCCGGGAGGCGGAGGUUGCCGUGAGCCACCGCACUUUGGCCUGGGUGACAGAGCAAGACUCCCUCUCAGAAAAAAAAAUUAAAAAAAUAGAAACAGCCGGGGAGUGGAGGGUGUGGUCAGAAAGCCUCAGGGACCUGCUUCAGCCUUCAGGGAGUUCAGAUGAGGCACAAUGAAGCCACUGGCCUCCACUCAGCCAUUCUUCCCUGCAGCUCUUUUUUUUUUUUUUUUUUUUGAGACAAUCUCGCUCCAUCACCCAGGCUGGAGUGCAGUGGCACAAUCUCGACUCACUGCAACCUCUGCCUCCUGGGUUCAAGUGAUUCUCCUGCCUCAGCCUCCUGAGUAGCUGGGACUACAGGGGUGCGCCCCCAUGCCCAGCUAAUUUUUGUAUUUUUAGUAGAGACGGGGUUUCACCAUGUUGGCCAGGCUGGUCUCCAACUCCUGGCCUCAGGUGAUCCACCCAUCUCGGCCUCCCAAAGUGCUGGGAUUCCAGGCGUGAGCCACCGCGCCCAGCCCCUGCAAUACGUCAACAGUCCCUAGAUUCAGGCAACAUGGAGUUGCAGCCAAGGAACUUUGAGGUAGUGACCAAUGCAGGGAGGUCUGACAGAGAAUCAGCAGGAUCCAUUUCAUGGCCACCACACAUCUGACUGACUCCUUCUUGGGCUAAGCAAAUACUUUUGUGGGCAGUGACACUGGCAGCUGCUGGGGUCUUGGCAGGAGGUUGGAUGGAGGUCUUCUCCCAGAGCAGUGUCCAGCUUGCAGGAAUGCUCCCUGCGUCUCAGUUGUGCCCAUUCCAGGUCCAGGGGAAAGAAGUGACCCGCUUCCCCUCUGAAAGCAGAUGUGGUCCCAACAAGCAAACACGGUCUCCAUCUCCAGCACCACAACUGCCACGGAGCAGAGGGAGGCCUCCCUGUGGAGCAGCCCUUCCCUGUGGCCUCAGCCCAUGCCCUCCUGCCCAGCCCCCAGUGGUGCUGCUGGAGGGUCUGACUCCACGGGCUCCCGCUGACCUUGCCGUUCCUUCCCCUCAUCUCGUAGCGCCUGGCCCCUGGAGGAAGGUGGGUAGGAAUUUGACACCGGAUAAAUAAAUGUUUGAGGGGCAAGAGAGAUGGGACAGAGUUCACCCAACAGGACAGACGAGGCUGGCAGUCACAGCAGAGGGCAGGCACUCAGGUCUGGAGAGGCAGGGCAUGGAGACAGGGACCCACACUCUGGAAGGUUUCUCGACUCCCCCGAGGGGCUGGCCAGUUCUGUCUUCCUUCUGCCCACUCUGUGGGGAGGAGCCUCUCUGGGAUAGCGUCCCCUCACUCCUCUCCCAGCCUCGUUUAUCUUCACCACAGUACAGAAGGGGGCCCCUCUCCAGGCCUCACCACUUAACUUUUCUUGUACAUGGAAAGACAAGCCUCUGCUAGAGGCCUGGCAAGGGUUCCCCUUCAGAGCCAGCCAGUGCUCUGCUGCUGUAAUCUCCAGGGACCCUGCCGGCCACGGCCCCCAUGCAGCUCCCUCCCUCAAUCCAACCCUCUUUGGGCUUAUCACCCUCAAGGUCUAGAGUGCACCAGGGUUGGCUGCUCUGCCAAGUCCUGUUGAGACUCCAAAAGCAUAGUCUGUCUUUAUUAGGGUGACCUUCAUAUCAGACUCCCAGGUAACUCAAGAUGAUAGCUUUGCAAUAUAGUGCCUCCUUUUAUUCCUAUUUGUGAGUUUCUCCGCUUUCCUCACUAGACUGAGAGGGUCUUGAGGGUAGGAGCUUUGUUUUAGUUAUCUCUCUAUCCCUGGCCCCUAAGACACUACCUGGCUCAGCAAACCAACCUUUGAGACAAAGCAACAUUAUAACACUACAUUCAUAUAGCAGAUCAUUUCAUGACCCACAUUCUCCUUCCUUUUUACGAAGAAAUGGGCUCAGGAUGUCUUGUCCAGCAUUAUGGAGUGAACGUCAGCUCCAGGAAGCAGAGACUUCUGGCCCUUUGUUCACCAUUUCCCCAGAACCUAGGGUGGUGACUCACCUAUAAGUGCUCAAAAAACAUGUGGCGAAUGGAGGACCAGAGCUAGGCUCUGAAUGAGGCCUCCUGGAUCUCACGCAGGGGAUGGAGAGUAAGGACCAGCCCCUCUACCUCAUGCUUUCUUCCUGCUAUCUCGUAAGAGCCCAACAUCCUUCUGUCCUGAGCAAGCCACAAGCUGCAGCCCUGCCUUGACAAAAUGGCAAAUGCCAGCCCCUCUGGCAGCAUGACACCUUGGUCCUGUGUGCUGCAGAGUGCCUCAUGUGUUGAACUGUGUGCCCUCAGAAGCAUGCCAUGCCCCCGCUCUGCUGGAGCAGUGGCAGAUGUCACCCUUCCUAGAUAAAUCCUGGACGGCUCCACGACUGGCUUUUAGCCCUCAACACUUGGCCUACAUUCUUUCUGGCUUGGUUGGAGAAGGAAAGAAGCAGUUGGAGGCAUGACUGCUAUUGUUCCUUGGCUUCUCUCCAUUUGUCUCAAACUUUCCUAAUAGAGCAAAAUUGCUGAGUGGUCUCUAUUUACCAACAUGAAACAGAAAAAUACCAUCUCAGGCUCCAUAUUCCAUGUCCCUGUUGAAUACAGAUCCCCGAACUGAGAAAUAAGAAACAACUACAUACGAAGUAAUACUUGAAAAUGUUUCUCUUGUAAUACUUCCAUAUCCAAAGCAUUUGAAUAUAUUUAUUUUAUUGAUGUAGGUCUGCCAACUCUUCCUUCUCAGGAAGGACUGUUUUUAUUCCAAACAUGUAUAUAUAAGGUUAAAAUGUAUUUUUUAAAAUAAGAUAAUUAUUGAUAGUUGUUUUUAAAAUAGCCUUGCUUAGCAAAAUAAAUGUUGGCAACCCUAAGUUUGUUCUAUUAUAAUAUUAUUGAAAUUACAUUGAAUUCUGAAAUCCAUGUCAACUUGAAGUUACCAAGUUUUAACCACUGUUAGAAAAUAAGCAGGAAUGAAAUCUGUUUCAAGCGUUUCAAUUUCAAUACAAUUUAAUAAACAGGCUUUGAGCAUCUACCCCCA